GCAAAGCCCCUCAUUUUGGCAGAACUUACCAUGUCGACCAGCCGCAAAUUAAAGAGUCAUGGCAUGAGGAGGAGCAAGAGCCGAUCUCCUCACAAGGGAGUCAAGAGAGGUGGCAGCAAAAGAAAAUACCGUAAGGGCAACCUGAAAAGUAGGAAACGGGGCGAUGACGCCAAUCGCAAUUACCGCUCCCACUUGUGAGCCCCCAGCGGGCUCUGCCCUGGUGCGCUUCACACAGCACCAAGCAGCAACAAGAACAGCAGAAGGGGAACUGCCAAGGAGACCUGAUGUUAGAUCAAAGCCAGAGAGGAGCCUAUGGAAUGUGGAUCAAAUGCCAGUUGUGACGAAAUGAGGAAUGUAUAUGUUGGCUGUUUUUCCCCAACAUCUCAAUAAAACUUUGAAAGCAGAAA